AGUGUUCGGCUGGGGCAGGCACGCUGUGGCUGGCUACUUCCCUUCCUCCCAUCCCCCUUGGGCCAAACGGGAUCGGUGCUUCUGGUGAGACGCCUCCCCAUGCACAUCACUCCCAGGUGCCCUAGGGGGCACAUUUCCCACAACUCCCAGAGGGCAGGUUUCUAGAAAGUGCCACCAGUGGGGAGGCGCCACAACUUCACUGCCAUUUUGUGAGGUGCCGCCGUCUCUCCUCCAGCAAGGAAACAAUGACCGAUAAAACAGAGAAGGUGGCUGUAGAUCCUGAAACUGUGUUUAAACGUCCCAGGGAAUGUGACAGUCCUUCGUAUCAGAAAAGGCAGAGGAUGGCCCUGUUGGCAAGGAAACAAGGAGCAGGAGACAGCCUUAUUGCAGGCUCUGCCAUGUCCAAAGAAAAGAAGCUUAUGACAGGACAUGCUAUUCCACCCAGCCAAUUGGAUUCUCAGAUUGAUGACUUCACUGGUUUCAGCAAAGAUAGGAUGAUGCAGAAACCUGGUAGCAAUGCACCUGUGGGAGGAAACGUUACCAGCAGUUUCUCUGGAGAUGACCUAGAAUGCAGAGAAACAGCCUUCUCUCCCAAAAGCCAACAAGAAAUUAAUGCUGAUAUAAAACGUCAAUUAGUGAAGGAACUCCGAUGCGUUGGACAAAAAUAUGAAAAAAUCUUCGAAAUGCUUGAAGGAGUGCAAGGACCUACUGCAGUCAGGAAACGAUUUUUUGAAUCCAUCAUCAAGGAAGCAGCAAGAUGUAUGAGACGAGACUUUGUUAAGCACCUUAAGAAGAAACUGAAACGUAUGAUUUGAGAAUACUUGUCCCUGGAGGAUUAUCACACCCCAAAUGCAUAAUCUCAUUAAUGAUUGAGGAGAGAAAAGGAUCAGAUUGCUGUUUUCUACAAUGGAGCAGGAUAUUGCUGAAGUCUCCUGGCAUAUGUUACCGAAUCAACUGGCCUUCCAGAGGCUAAGAAAUUUCUGUUAGUAAAAGAUGUUCUUUUUCCCAAAGCGUUUUAUUUGAAAGGAUAACUUGUGUUUUGGUUAUUUUGUAUUCCCACCUGUGCUGGUAGAUAUUAUUAACCCAUUAGGUAAAUACUAUUACAGUCGUGGUUUCUGCAGCAGCUCACACUGAUGUAGCUGGCGUUUAUAACUACCUUCUUUCGCUACCCGUUUCGCAUUCCCUUUGCCCUGAGAUAGCAUGUCAGUUGGUCAUGAUGCUUGGCCUGGCAGGAUGACUCAAACCUUCAUUACGGAAGAGUCUGAACCAUUAGAUAUCCUGCCUGGAUGGGGUUGCUGUGAUUUUCCAUUAACUCUAAUCGAAAAACACGGGAGGACUAAGAAGCUCUCUAGACAUAUCACACAUACU